UGCUUAAAGGAGCUGAUGGAGCUGAAAGCCAAGGCUCAAGAACUACAUGAAGAAUGCAAAAGCCUCAGGAGCCGAUGCGAUCAACUGGAAGAAAGGGUAUCAGUGAUGGAAGAUGAAAUGAAUUUUAAAACAUUUUAAUGAGAAUUUCUUAAUUUUAUUCUCUGUGAUAGGAUGGACUGGUGCAAUUUUUUUUUUUUUUUUUAACAAACGAGGGAAAUUAAGCUAGAAAGCAUAGGUGGGGACCUAGGAUUAAAUGCCAUAUAUUCUAAUUCCAAGUCCAAGUCCAAUCCUCUUUUCAUUAUGCCACCCUGAUUUUCAACAUCAGUAUGGUAUCAUUGACUUAAAAUCUAGGGAAAAUAAGUUAUAACUAAAAUAUCUUUACAUUAUGUCUAACAUAUGACCUGUAUGAGCAAAAAUCAGUUUUGAGAAAGCAUCAAUGAAGCUGAGAUCUCCCCAAGUCAUUACUUACCCACAAAGAAAAGCAUUGUUUCCCAAUGAAUAAAUAAUUGCAGGAAAUAGUUUGCAGUAAUCAAUUUGUAUGAGUAAAAAUAAAGAUAUUUUAUAUUGAGUAUUUCCUCACAAUGACUGUAUACUACUCAAAAGCCCUAGCAAUUUUUUUUGUCUAACUUUCAAAUAAUCUAAGAUAAUGAUGGCUAACAGUUGUUUUAGACUAGAACUUGUGAAAUAUGUUUUAUGUUUGUUAUUUCAUUUAUUUCUCUCAAUUAUACUAUGAGAAAUUUCCUGUUAUCCACUGAGAUUUGGCAAGAAGGUAUUUAUAGAAAACCACAAAGUUAGUUAGCAUUUUUGCCUUGAUGAUUUGACUUUAUACCCCAUAUGUUUAAUCACUAUAGUCUACAGCCUGUGUACAUGAAAGCUUGCAGGUAAAUUGUAAUAGAUAUAUUGAUAUGACACAGGUAUACUCUGUAAUAGAUACAUUGAUCAUAACACAAGUAUACUCUGACACUGGGAGCUCAUCUUUACCCCUGUGUGUGGUACACAUAGAAAAACUUAUGUCAAUCCCUGCCAACUGUACAUGAAGAUCAGGUAAAGAUAUCAAUGGAACAAUGAUAUAGAAUGUGCACAAAAUAUACGUCUUUACUUUAAUAAUUCCUCACUGUCAGGAAUGGAAGAGAGCCAGUCAACAGCCUCAUUUUAUGGAUGGAAACACUGAGCUCCAAAAGCUGAAAAUGCUUCAUUGCUUAUGUGGAAGUCCAAGAGAAGAACCCAGGUCUGCUUAGUCCCAAUCAAUUCAGGGACCAAAUACUAUUUCCAGAGUUUUAUCCACUAUAUCUUAUGAUACCUGGAAAUCAAAUUCCUUCUACUAUGAUAUGACCUAGUACGUAUAUCUAUAAAGAACUUUAUAGUUUACAAAACACUUUCAUAGCCCAGUUGUAGGGCUGUAAGUGGCAGACGGGUCUACUGGCUCAGGGUCUAAAUAACGUUUGUUCUGCAGACUUACAUAAGAAAGCUAAGGAAACAUCUAGCUUCAUAGGAGACCAGGGCAGGCUUAGUUCUGCAAUCUAUAUGACAUCCAAAGUAGACACCAGACUGUUGAUAAUGCUGACCUUUUUCUUCCAGCAUUUAUCAAAACUCACGACCUUAAAAGUAUCCCCAAUCUUUCUGAAAUUGAAGUCUAGAUUUGGUCUACAAUGGAUACAUUCCCAGAAUCCUUUUAAUAUUUAUAAAUGAAUUUAAAAAUAGUUAUUGCUGUUCAAAUUUUAAAACCCGCCUAUAAGCAAAAUAUAGAAGAUACAAUUAUGGAAUACAGAACAGAACAUGCAUAUUUUUAAUGUAUGAAAUAUAAAAGUAAAAAUAGAGGUGAAAAAUCGCUAGACAAAAAUGCUGAUUGAGGGAAGUGUAUGGAGACAGAUGAACUACUUAUUGGGUUAUGAGAUACUGUCUAAAGAUGAUGACAUAGAAAUAGUGACUAAAGUACAUUACUUUAGGUUACAAAGUUAACAAGCAGAAUUUUAAAAAGUCAUGAUAUGCCUAUCAAAAACUGGGAUGAAUGAAAAGGAAAUGUAAAUUAAUACUUUUUUCCUCCAUAGGUGGGAGUCAACAAAUAAUUUUAGCUUGUAAGGCAAUAGAUGUAUAUUAUUAAGAAUUAUGAUGGCAAUAAUCUAAAAACAGAAAUGGUUCAAAUGAGUUCCCACUGAAGUGUGAUGCUGAUGAUAAAAGACUGGUUUUUCAUUAUAAACUGUUUAAUGUCAAUGGAAUUUAUAAGUAUUUCUUACAAUGACAUAUAUAUUAACUUUAUUAACUUUCUUUCCUUCUUUAUUCUUAGGAAGAGUAAAUCAUUCCCACAUGGGAAGCUGCUAACUUGCCGUCAUAUGAAUGUGAAGUAAAUUUGUUUUUAAAAUUUUACCUUUUGAAGGUUAGGUAUUGGAGAAGAAGUGAUUUCAUUGAGAUUUGUCUCUCUGUGUGAUCAAUCAGCAUUUGCAUCUUUAUGGUCUUUAUGAAUCCUUCUCAUCAUUGUUUUCAUUAUAAAACUCCACCAAGCAGCUCAGGAGAACACAAUGAACCCAGGAGACUCAUGGGCUUAACGCAACCUGAACAUUUACAAGGUAUAGAAUGUGCCAAACAGACGAAACAGAUGGUUGACUGCAGUCAUUAUAAAAAGUUACCACCAGGACAACAGAGAUUUUGUCAUCAUAUGUAUGAUCCAAUUUGUGGAUCUGAUGGCAAAACUUAUAAAAAUGAUUGCUUCUUCUGUUCUAAAGUUAAGAAAACUGACGGCACACUUAAAUUUGUACAUUUUGGAAAAUGUUAAAUCUAUCUUGUGAGUCCAAAAUAUCUUUUAAUGCAUCUAUUCACAAGAGUCACAUUUCUGUUCCCAUAUUAUCUAUGCCACAUUGCCUACUCAUCACCAUAUGUAGAUUUCUUUGUAGAAUAAAGCAGAUAUAAGGGAAA